ACCCUGAAAGCUGUUUCUGUCUCUACCCUACUUGUUCCUCUGGUGAGCUAGGUUACUCAAACUUGCAAAAAAAAAAAUGCCUAAACUCCUACAAGGCGUCAUCACUGUCAUCGAUGUUUUCUACCAAUAUGCCACCCAGCAUGGGGAGUAUGAUACGUUGAACAAGGCAGAGCUGAAAGAACUUCUGGAAAAUGAGUUUCAUCAAAUUCUGAAGAAUCCAAACGAUCCAGAUACUGUGGAUAUCAUCUUGCAAAGUCUGGAUCGAGACCAUAACAAGAAAGUGGAUUUUACUGAGUAUCUUCUGAUGAUAUUCAAGCUGGUUCAGGCUCGUAAUAAAAUCAUUGGCAAAGAUUACUGCCAAGUUUCAGGGUCAAAGCUGAGAGAUGACACUCACCAGCACCAAGAGGAACAAGAAGAAACUGAAAAAGAGGAGAACAAACGGCAAGAAUCCUCUUUUAGUCAUUCAAGUUGGAGUGCAGGAGAGAAUGAUUCCUAUUCCAGAAACGUCAGAGGAAGUCUUAAACCUGGGACUGAAUCCAUAUCCAGAAGACUGAGUUUUCAAAGAGACUUUUCUGGCCAACAUAACUCCUACUCAGGUCAGUCUUCCAGCUAUGGUGAGCAAAACUCCGACUCCCAUCAGUCUUCAGGCCGCGGCCAAUGUGGGUCUGGGUCAGGGCAGUCUCCCAACUAUGGCCAACACGGCUCUGGCUCCGGACAGUCUUCCAGCAAUGACACACAUGGGUCUGGCUCAGGCCAGUCUUCUGGCUUUAGUCAACACAAGUCUAGCUCAGGGCAGUCCUCUGGUUACAGUCAGCAUGGAUCUGGCUCAGGUCACUCCUCUGGCUACGGACAACACGGCUCUAGGUCAGGACAGUCAUCUAGGGGUGAACGACACAGAUCUAGCUCAGGUUCGUCUUCCAGCUAUGGUCAGCAUGGGUCUGGUUCCCGUCAGUCUUUGGGCCACGGCCGACAAGGGUCUGGAUCUCGCCAGUCUCCUAGCCACGUCCGACAUGGGUCCGGUUCGGGGCACUCCUCCAGCCACGGCCAACACGGGUCUGGCUCAAGUUACUCUUACAGCCGUGGCCAUUAUGAGUCUGGCUCAGGCCAGACUUCUGGCUUUGGGCAACAUGAGUCUGGCUCAGGACAGUCCUCUGGCUAUAGUAAGCAUGGUUCUGGCUCAGGUCACUCCUCUAGCCAGGGACAACAUGGAUCUACGUCAGGGCAGGCAUCAAGCUCUGGCCAACAUGGCUCCAGCUCACGUCAGUCUUCCAGCUAUGGUCAGCAUGAGUCUGCCUCCCGUCACUCUUCAGGCCGCGGCCAACACAGCUCUGGAUCUGGCCAGUCUCCAGGCCACGGCCAGCGUGGGUCUGGGUCAGGGCAGUCUCCCAGCUCCGGCCAACAUGGGACUGGCUUUGGUCGAUCUUCCAGCAGUGGCCCAUAUGUGUCUGGUUCAGGCUACUCUUCUGGCUUUGGUCACCACGAGUCUAGCUCAGAGCAUUCCUCUGGUUACACUCAGCAUGGAUCUGGCUCAGGUCACUCCUCCGGCCACGGACAACACGGCUCUAGGUCAGGACAGUCAUCUAGGGGUGAACGACAAGGAUCUAGUGCAGGUUCAUCUUCCAGCUAUGGUCAGCAUGGGUCUGGCUCCCGUCAAUCUUUGGGACACAGCCGACAUGGGUCUGGAUCUGGCCAGUCUCCUAGCCCUAGCCGUGGCCGACAUGAGUCUGGUUCCAGGCAGUCUUCCAGCUAUGGCCCACAUGGGUAUGGCUCAGGGAGGUCUUCAAGCCGUGGCCCAUAUGAGUCUGGCUCCGGUCACUCUUCUGGCUUAGGUCACCAAGAGUCUCGCUCAGGACAGUCCUCUGGCUACGGUCAACACGGAUCUAGCUCGGGUCAUUCCUCUACCCAUGGGCAACAUGGUUCUACAUCAGGACAGUCAUCGAGCUGUGGCCAACAUGGAGCUACCUCAGGUCAGUCUUCCAGCCACGGUCAGCAUGGCUCUGGCUCAAGUCAGUCUUCUCGCUAUGGCCAACAGGGCUCUGGAUCUGGCCAGUCUCCUAGUCGCGGCCGACAUGGGUCCGAUUUUGGGCACUCUUCCAGCUACGGCCAACAUGGGUCUGGCUCCGGUUGGUCUUCAAGCAAUGGCCCACAUGGGUCUGUCUCAGGCCAGUCUUCCGGCUUUGGUCACAAGUCUGGCUCAGGGCAGUCCUCUGGUUACAGUCAGCAUGGAUCUGGCUCAAGUCACUCCUCCGGCUACAGAAAACACGGCUCUAGGUCAGGACAGUCAUCUAGGAGUGAACAACACGGAUCUAGCUCAGGUUUGUCUUCCAGCUAUGGUCAGCAUGGGUCGGGCUCCCAUCAAUCUUCGGGCCACGGCCGACAAGGGUCUGGAUCUGGCCACUCUCCUAGCCGUGUCCGACAUGGGUCCAGUUCAGGGCACUCCUCCAGCCACGGCCAACACGGGUCUGGCACAAGUUGUUCUUCCAGCUGUGGCCAUUAUGAGUCUGGCUCAGGCCAGGCUUCUGGUUUUGGGCAACACGAGUCUGGCUCAGGACAGGGCUAUAGUCAGCAUGGUUCUGCCUCAGGUCACUUCUCUAGCCAGGGACGACAUGGAUCUACGUCAGGGCAGUCAUCAAGCUCCGGCCAACAUGACUCUAGCUCAGGUCAAUCUUCCAGCUAUGGUCAGCAUGAGUCUGCCUCCCAUCACGCUUCGGGCCGCGGCCGACAUGGCUCUGGAUCUGGCCAGUCUCCAGGCCACGGCCAGCGUGGGUCUGGGUCAGGGCAGUCUCCCAGCUAUGGCCGACAUGGGUCUGGCUCCGGUCGGUCUUCCAGCAGUGGCCGACAUGGGUCUGGCUCAGGCCAGUCUUCUGGCUUUGGUCACAAGUCUAGCUCAGGGCAGUCCUCUGGUUACACUCAGCAUGGAUCUGGCUCAGGUCACUCCUCCAGCUACGAACAACACGGCUCUAGGUCAGGACAGUCAUCUAGGAGCGAACAACAUGGAUCUAGCUCAGGUUCGUCUUCCAGCUAUGGUCAGCAUGGGUCUGGCUCCCGUCAGUCUUUGGGCCACGGCCAACAUGGGUCUGGAUCUGGCCAGUCUCCUAGCCCUAGCCGUGGCCGACAUGGGUCUGGUUCCGGGCAGUCUUCCAGCUAUGGCCCAUAUAGGUCUGGCUCAGGGUGGUCUUCAAGCCGUGGCCCAUAUGAGUCUGGCUCCGGUCACUCUUCUGGCUUAGGUCACCGAGAGUCUCGCUCAGGACAGUCCUCUGGCUACGGUCAACAUGGAUCUAGCUCAGGUCAUUCCUCUACCCAUGGGCAACACGGUUCUACAUCAGGACAGUCAUCGAGCUGUGGCCAACAUGGAGCUAGCUCAGGUCAGUCUUCCAGCCACGGUCAGCAUGGCUCUGGCUCAAGUCAGUCUUCUGGCUAUGGCCGACAGGGCUCUGGAUCUGGCCAGUCUCCAGGCCACGGCCAGCGUGGGUCUGGGUCAAGGCAGUCUCCCAGCUACGGCCGACAUGGGUCUGGCUCCGGUCGGUCUUCCAGCAGUGGCCAACAUGGGUCUGGCUUAGGCGAGUCUUCUGGCUUUGGUCACCACGAGUCUAGCUCAGGGCAGUCCUCUAGUUACAGUCAGCAUGGGUCUGGCUCAGGUCACUCCUCUGGCUACGGACAACACGGCUCUAGAUCAGGACAGUCAUCUAGGGGUGAACGACACGGAUCUAGCUCAGGUUCGUCUUCCCACUAUGGUCAGCAUGGGUCUGGCUCCCGUCAGUCUUCGGGCCACGGCCGACAAGGGUCUGGAUCUGGCCAUUCCCCUAGCCGCGGCCGACAUGGGUCCGGUUUGGGGCACUCCUCCAGCCACGGCCAACAUGGGUCUGGCUCAGGUCGUUCUUCCAGCCGUGGCCCAUAUGAGUCUCGCUCGGGUCACUCUUCUGUCUUUGGUCAACAUGAGUCUGGCUCAGGACAUUCCUCUGCUUACAGUCAGCAUGGUAGUGGCUCAGGGCACUUCUGUAGCCAAGGACAGCAUGGUUCUACAUCAGGACAGUCAUCAACCUUUGACCAGGAGGGAUCUAGCACAGGCCAGUCUUCCAGCUAUGGCCACCGUGGCUCUGGCUCCAGUCAGUCUUCUGGCUAUGGCCGACAUGGGGCUGGAUCUGGCCAGUCUCCUAGUCGCGGCCGACAUGGGUCCGGUUCUGGGCACUCUUCCAGCUACGGCCAACAUGGGUCUGGCUCCGGUUGGUCUUCCAGCAGUGGCCGACAUGGGUCUGGCUCAGGUCAGUCUUCUGGAUUUGGUCACCACGAGUCUAGCUCAUGGCAGUCCUCUGGUUGCACUCAGCAUGGAUCUGGCUCAGGUCACUCCUCCAGCUACGAACAACACGGCUCUAGGUCAGGACAGUCAUCUAGGGGUGAACGACACGGAUCUAGCUCAGGUUCAUCUUCCAGCUAUGGUCAGCAUGGGUCUGGCUCCCGUCAGUCUUUGGGCCACGGCCAACAUGGGUCUGGAUCUGGCCAGUCUCCUAGCCCUAGCCGUGGCCGACAUGGGUCUGGUUCUGGGCAGUCUUCCAGCUACAGCCCAUAUGGGUCUGGCUCAGGGUGGUCUUCCAGCCGUGGCCCAUAUGAGUCUGGCUCCAGUCACUCUUCUGGCUUAGGUCACCGAGAGUCUCGCUCAGGACAGUCCUCUGGCUACGGUCAACAUGGAUCUAGCUCAGGUCAUUCCUCUACCCAUGGGCAACAUGGUUCUACAUCAGGACAGUCAUCGAGCUGUGGCCAACAUGGAGCUAGCUCAGGUCAGUCUUCCAGCCACGGUCAGCAUGGCUCUGGCUCAAGUCAGUCUUCUGGCUAUGGCCGACAGGGCUCUGGAUCUGGCCAGUCUCCAGGCCACGGCCAGCGUGGGUCUGGGUCAAGGCAGUCUCCCAGCUACGGCCGACAUGGGUCUGGCUCCGGUCGGUCUUCCAGCAGUGGCCAACAUGGGUCUGGCUUAGGCGAGUCUUCUGGCUUUGGUCACCACGAGUCUAGCUCAGGGCAGUCCUCUAGUUACAGUCAGCAUGGGUCUGGCUCAGGUCACUCCUCUGGCUACGGACAACACGGCUCUAGAUCAGGACAGUCAUCUAGGGGUGAACGACACGGAUCUAGCUCACGUUCGUCUUCCCGCUAUGGUCAGCAUGGGUCUGGCUCCCGUCAGUCUUCGGGCCACGGCCGACAAGGGUCUGGAUCUGGCCAGUCCCCUAGCCGCGGCCGACAUGGGUCCGGUUUGGGGCACUCCUCCAGCCACGGCCAACAUGGGUCUGGCUCAGGUCGUUCUUCCAGCCGUGGCCCAUAUGAGUCUCGCUCGGGUCACUCUUCUGUCUUUGGUCAACAUGAGUCUGGCUCAGGACAUUCCUCUGCUUACAGUCAGCAUGGUAGUGGCUCAGGGCACUUCUGUAGCCAAGGACAGCAUGGUUCUACAUCAGGACAGUCAUCAACCUUUGACCAGGAGGGAUCUAGCACAGGUCAGUCUUCCAGCCACGGUCAGCAUGGCUCUGGCUCAAGUCAGUCUUCUAGCUAUGGCCAACAGGGCUCUGGAUCUGGCCAGUCUCCUAGUCGCGGCCGACAUGGGUCCGGUUCCGGGCACUCUUCCAGCUACGGCCAACAUGGGUCUGGCUCCGGUUGGUCUUCCAGCAGUGGCCGACAUGGGUCUGGCUCAGGUCAGUCUUCUGGAUUUGGUCACCAUGAGUCUAGCUCAUGGCAGUCCUCUGGUUACACUCAGCAUGGAUCUGGCUCAGGUCACUCCUCCAGCUACGAACAACACGGCUCUAGGUCAGGACAGUCAUCUAGGGGUGAACAACACGGAUCUAGCUCAGGUUCAUCUUCCAGCUAUGGUCAGCAUGGGUCUGGCUCCCGUCAGUCUUUGGGCCACGGCCAACAUGGGUCUGGAUCUGGCCAGUCUCCUAGCCCUAGCCGUGGCCGACAUGGGUCUGGUUCUGGGCAGUCUUCCAGCUACGGCCCAUAUGGGUCUGGCUCAGGGUGGUCUUCCAGCCGUGGCCCAUAUGAGUCUGGCUCCGGUCACUCUUCUGGCUUAGGUCACCGAGAGUCUCGCUCAGGACAGUCCUCUGGCUACGGUCAACAUGGAUCUAGCUCAGGUCAUUCCUCUACCCAUGGGCAACAUGGUUCUGCAUCAGGACAGUCAUCGAGCUGUGGCCAACAUGGAGCUAGCUCAGGUCAGUCUUCCAGCCACGGUCAGCAUGGCUCUGGCUCAAGUCAGUCUUCUGGCUAUGGCCGACAGGGCUCUGGAUCUGGCCAGUCUCCAGGCCACGGCCAGCGUGGGUCUGGGUCAAGGCAGUCUCCCAGCUAUGGCCGACAUGGGUCUGGCUCCGGUCGGUCUUCCAGCAGUGGCCAACAUGGGCCUGGCUUAGGCGAGUCUUCUGGCUUUGGUCACCACGAGUCUAGCUCAGGGCAGUCCUCUAGUUACAGUCAGCAUGGGUCUGGCUCAGGUCACUCCUCUGGCUACGGACAACACGGCUCUAGAUCAGGACAGUCAUCUAGGGGUGAACGACACGGAUCUAGCUCAGGUUCGUCUUCCCGCUAUGGUCAGCAUGGGUCUGGCUCCCGUCAGUCUUCGGGCCACGGCCGACAAGGGUCUGGAUCUGGCCAUUCCCCUAGCCGCGGCCGACAUGGGUCCGGUUCGGGGCACUCCUCCAGCCACGGCCAACAUGGGUCUGGCUCAGGUCGUUCUUCCAGCCGUGGCCCAUAUGAGUCUCGCUCGGGUCACUCUUCUGUCUUUGGUCAACAUGAGUCUGGCUCAGGACAUUCCUCUGCUUACAGUCAGCAUGGUAGUGGCUCAGGGCACUUCUGUAGCCAAGGACAGCAUGGUUCUACAUCAGGACAGUCAUCAACCUUUGACCAGGAGGGAUCUAGCACAGGUCAGUCUUCCAGCCACGGUCAGCAUGGCUCUGGCUCAAGUCAGUCUUCUAGCUAUGGCCAACAGGGCUCUGGAUCUGGCCAGUCUCCUAGUCGCGGCCGACAUGGGUCCGGUUCCGGGCACUCUUCCAGCUACGGCCAACAUGGGUCUGGCUCCGGUUGGUCUUCCAGCAGUGGCCGACAUGGGUCUGGCUCAGGUCAGUCUUCUGGAUUUGGUCACCACGAGUCUAGCUCAUGGCAGUCCUCUGGUUACACUCAGCAUGGAUCUGGCUCAGGUCACUCCUCCAGCUACGAACAACACGGCUCUAGGUCAGGACAGUCAUCUAGGGGUGAACGACACGGAUCUAGCUCAGGUUCAUCUUCCAGCUAUGGUCAGCAUGGGUCUGGCUCCCGUCAGUCUUUGGGCCACGGCCAACAUGGGUCUGGAUCUGGCCAGUCUCCUAGCCCUAGCCGUGGCCGACAUGGGUCUGGUUCUGGGCAGUCUUCCAGCUACAGCCCAUAUGGGUCUGGCUCAGGGUGGUCUUCCAGCCGUGGCCCAUAUGAGUCUGGCUCCGGUCACUCUUCUGGCUUAGGUCACCGAGAGUCUCGCUCAGGACAGUCCUCUGGCUACGGUCAACAUGGAUCUAGCUCAGGUCAUUCCUCUACCCAUGGGCAACAUGGUUCUACAUCAGGACAGUCAUCGAGCUGUGGCCAACAUGGAGCUAGCUCAGGUCAGUCUUCCAGCCACGGUCAGCAUGGCUCUGGCUCAAGUCAGUCUUCUGGCUAUGGCCGACAGGGCUCUGGAUCUGGCCAGUCUCCAGGCCACGGCCAGCGUGGGUCUGGGUCAAGGCAGUCUCCCAGCUACGGCCGACAUGGGUCUGGCUCCGGUCGGUCUUCCAGCAGUGGCCAACAUGGGUCUGGCUUAGGCGAGUCUUCUGGCUUUGGUCACCACGAGUCUAGCUCAGGGCAGUCCUCUAGUUACAGUCAGCAUGGGUCUGGCUCAGGUCACUCCUCUGGCUACGGACAACACGGCUCUAGAUCAGGACAGUCAUCUAGGGGUGAACGACACGGAUCUAGCUCAGGUUCGUCUUCCCACUAUGGUCAGCAUGGGUCUGGCUCCCGUCAGUCUUCGGGCCACGGCCGACAAGGGUCUGGAUCUGGCCAGUCCCCUAGCCGCGGCCGACAUGGGUCCGGUUUGGGGCACUCCUCCAGCCACGGCCAACAUGGGUCUGGCUCAGGUCGUUCUUCCAGCCGUGGCCCAUAUGAGUCUCGCUUGGGUCACUCUUCUGUCUUUGGUCAACAUGAGUCUGGCUCAGGACAUUCCUCUGCUUACAGUCAGCAUGGUAGUGGCUCAGGGCACUUCUGUAGCCAAGGACAGCAUGGUUCUACAUCAGGACAGUCAUCAACCUUUGACCAGGAGGGAUCUAGCACAGGCCAGUCUUCCAGCUAUGGCCACCGUGGCUCUGGCUCCAGUCAGUCUUCUGGCUAUGGCCGACAUGGGGCUGGAUCUGGCCAGUCUCUUAGCCACGGCCGACACGGGUCUGGUUCAGGGCAGUCUUCCAGCUACGGCCAACAUGGGUCUGGCUCAGGACAGUCCUCUGGUUAUAGUCAGCAUGGAAGUGGCUCAGGGCAAGAUGGGUAUUCUUAUUGCAAAGGAGGAAGUAACCAUGAUGGGGGAAGUUCUGGCUCAUAUUUUCUCAGUUUUCCUAGUAGCACUUCACCCUAUGAAUAUGUCCAAGAGCAGAGGUGCUACUUUUAUCAGUGAAUAAUAAACAUAAAUGCAAUUUACUCAAGUAGCAAUUUAAGAAAUAGGAAAGUCAUCUAUGAAUUCAUCAUGAAAGACAAGCAAUCCAUCAUGAAAUUCGUUCUAAAAGUGAAUCAAUGCAUUUCUGUCUCUUUCUUUAGAGCCUAAAACUGUAGCAUAUAUCUUGUUAUGGGGUUCCUUCCAAAGACUGUUAGGCAUUUGUGCUACUUUGUUAGAAAAUACUGAGUGGAAUAACUUGUUAGAAUGAGGGUUAAACUUUGAGGAAUAAUGAAAAGCUUUUAAAGAGCUUUGGGUUUAGUUGGAGUUGUCUUUUUGAGAGCUCAUCAUUCAUUUAUAGAUGGUGCCAAAGCUAACCUUACAUUUCUUAGAAGCAAAAUAUUACAAAUGCAUUACCAGUCCUAGAUACAAAGCUUUGUUUUACAGCAAUUAGUGUACCCUAAUUUUUAGUGUGCCCCAAGUUUGGUGUGUCCCAAUUUUUGGUAUUGUGGCAGAAGGUGAAGGCUCUGAAAGCAAAGAUGCAGCAGCGGUAGUGUCUUUACUUAUCAAAACCAUCAAGUCCUUUUUCUUGGGUAUAUAUUUAAUCAGUAAGUUAAUUAGUGGCAUAAAAAAGUAGCAUCAGGGUCUUUUCCCAAGCCAGUGAGCAAGAGCAUUAUUUCAUAAAGAAUAGGGAUUUAUCAUUUCAGGAAAAAAAAAAACAUUCAAAUGUGGGCUUUAGCUUGUUUUCAGCAGAAAGAUCUUGCUCCCUAUUUCUAAGAGGCUGCUCAAUAUUGGGAAAUAUAUUGAGGAGUUAUUCCAUGGAAAUACAAUGCUUUCCACCUACUACUGUAGUUCAAUAACGUUUCCACCUGAAAAAAUAUCAUCCAUGCCCAGAUGAAAAGGAAGAGUAUCUGUCACUGCUACAUAGUUCCUUAAUUUGACUGUAACACAUUUGUUUCAAGUCUUUGGAUUCAAACAACCGGAUUGUAUUAAAAUUGACAAUAAAUAAAUGUUGAUUAAAUAC